ACGUGAUCCGCAGGGCGGCCGAGGCAGGAAGCUGUGAGUGCGCGGUUGCGGGGUCGCAUUGUGGCUACGGCUUUGCGUCCCCGGCGGGCAGCCCCAGGCUGGUCCCCGCCUCCGCUCUCCCCACCGGCGGGGAAAGCAGCUGGUGUGGGAGGAAAGGCUCCAUCCCCCGCCCCCUCUCUCCCGCUGUUGGCUGGCAGGAUCUUUUGGCAGUCCUGUGGCCUCGCUCCCCGCCCGGAUCCUCCUGACCCUGAGAUUCGCGGGUCUCACGUCCCGUGCACGCCUUGCUUCGGCCUCAGUUAAGCCUUUGUGGGCUCCAGGUCCCUGGUGAGAUUAGAAACGUUUGCAAACAUGUCCCGGAUCGAAAAGAUGAGCAUUCUGGGCGUGCGGAGUUUUGGAAUAGAGGACAAAGAUAAGCAAAUUAUCACUUUCUUCAGCCCCCUUACAAUUUUGGUUGGACCCAAUGGGGCGGGAAAGACGACCAUCAUUGAAUGUCUAAAAUAUAUUUGUACUGGAGAUUUCCCUCCUGGAACCAAAGGAAAUACAUUUGUACACGAUCCCAAGGUUGCUCAAGAAACAGAUGUGAGAGCCCAGAUUCGUCUGCAAUUUCGUGAUGUCAAUGGAGAACUUAUAGCUGUGCAAAGAUCUAUGGUGUGUACUCAGAAAAGCAAAAAGACAGAAUUUAAAACUCUGGAAGGAGUCAUUACUAGAACAAAGCAUGGUGAAAAGGUCAGUCUGAGCUCUAAGUGUGCAGAAAUUGACCGAGAAAUGAUCAGUUCUCUUGGGGUUUCCAAGGCUGUGCUAAAUAAUGUCAUUUUCUGUCAUCAAGAAGAUUCUAAUUGGCCUUUAAGUGAAGGAAAGGCUUUGAAGCAAAAGUUUGAUGAGAUUUUUUCAGCAACAAGAUACAUUAAAGCCUUAGAAACACUUCGGCAGGUACGUCAGACACAAGGUCAGAAAGUAAAAGAAUAUCAAAUGGAACUAAAAUAUCUGAAGCAAUAUAAGGAAAAAGCUUGUGAGAUUCGUGAUCAGAUUACAAGUAAGGAAGCCCAGUUAACAUCUUCAAAGGAAAUUGUCAAAUCCUAUGAGAAUGAACUUGAUCCAUUGAAGAAUCGUCUAAAAGAAAUUGAACAUAAUCUCUCUAAAAUAAUGAAACUUGACAAUGAAAUUAAAGCCUUGGAUAGCCGAAAGAAGCAAAUGGAGAAAGAUAAUAGUGAACUGGAAGAGAAAAUGGAAAAGGUUUUUCAAGGGACUGAUGAGCAACUAAAUGACUUAUAUCACAAUCACCAGAGAACAGUAAGGGAGAAAGAAAGGAAAUUGGUAGACUGUCAUCGUGAACUGGAAAAACUAAAUAAAGAAUCUAGGCUUCUCAAUCAGGAAAAAUCAGAACUGCUUGUUGAACAGGGUCGUCUACAGCUGCAAGCAGAUCGCCAUCAAGAACAUAUCCGAGCUAGAGAUUCAUUAAUUCAGUCUUUGGCAACACAGCUAGAAUUGGAUGGCUUUGAGCGUGGACCAUUCAGUGAAAGACAGAUUAAAAAUUUUCACAAACUUGUGAGAGAGAGACAAGAAGGGGAAGCAAAAACUGCCAACCAACUGAUGAAUGACUUUGCAGAAAAAGAGACUCUGAAACAAAAACAGAUAGAUGAGAUAAGAGAUAAGAAAACUGGACUGGGAAGAAUAAUUGAGUUAAAAUCAGAAAUCCUAAGUAAGAAGCAGAAUGAGCUGAAAAAUGUGAAGUAUGAAUUACAGCAGUUGGAAGGAUCUUCAGACAGGAUUCUUGAACUGGACCAGGAGCUCAUAAAAGCUGAACGUGAGUUAAGCAAGGCUGAGAAAAACAGCAAUGUAGAAACCUUAAAAAUGGAAGUAAUAAGUCUCCAAAAUGAAAAAGCAGACUUAGACAGGACCCUGCGUAAACUUGACCAGGAGAUGGAGCAGUUAAACCAUCAUACAACAACACGUACCCAAAUGGAGAUGCUGACCAAAGACAAAGCUGACAAAGAUGAACAAAUCAGAAAAAUAAAAUCUAGGCACAGUGAUGAAUUAACCUCACUGUUGGGAUAUUUUCCCAACAAAAAACAGCUUGAAGACUGGCUACAUAGUAAAUCAAAAGAAAUUAAUCAGACCAGGGACAGACUUGCCAAAUUGAACAAGGAACUAGCUUCAUCUGAGCAGAAUAAAAAUCAUAUAAAUAAUGAACUAAAAAGAAAGGAAGAGCAGUUGUCCAGUUACGAAGACAAGCUGUUUGAUGUUUGUGGUAGCCAGGAUUUUGAAAGUGAUUUAGACAGGCUUAAAGAGGAAAUUGAAAAAUCAUCAAAACAGCGAGCCAUGCUGGCUGGAGCCACAGCAGUUUACUCCCAGUUCAUUACUCAGCUAACAGACGAAAACCAGUCAUGUUGCCCCGUUUGUCAGAGAGUUUUUCAGACAGAGGCUGAGUUACAAGAAGUCAUCAGUGAUUUGCAGUCUAAACUGCGACUUGCUCCAGAUAAACUCAAGUCAACAGAAUCAGAGCUAAAAAAAAAGGAAAAGCGGCGUGAUGAAAUGCUGGGACUUGUGCCCAUGAGGCAAAGCAUAAUUGAUUUGAAGGAGAAGGAAAUACCAGAAUUAAGAAACAAACUGCAGAAUGUCAAUAGAGACAUACAGCGCCUAAAGAACGACAUAGAAGAACAAGAAACACUCUUGGGUACAAUAAUGCCUGAAGAAGAAAGUGCCAAAGUAUGCCUGACAGAUGUUACAAUUAUGGAGAGGUUCCAGAUGGAACUUAAAGAUGUUGAAAGAAAAAUUGCACAACAAGCAGCUAAGCUACAAGGAAUAGACUUAGAUCGAACUGUCCAACAAGUCAACCAGGAGAAACAAGAGAAACAGCACAAGUUAGACACAGUUUCUAGUAAGAUUGAAUUGAAUCGUAAGCUUAUACAGGACCAGCAGGAACAGAUUCAACAUCUAAAAAGUACAACAAAUGAGCUAAAAUCUGAGAAACUUCAGAUAUCCACUAAUUUGCAACGUCGUCAGCAACUGGAGGAGCAGACUGUGGAAUUAUCCACUGAAGUUCAGUCUUUGUACAGAGAGAUAAAGGAUGCUAAAGAGCAGGUAAGCCCUUUGGAAACAACAUUGGAAAAGUUCCAGCAAGAAAAAGAAGAAUUAAUCAACAAAAAAAAUACAAGCAACAAAAUAGCACAGGAUAAACUGAAUGAUAUUAAAGAGAAGGUUAAAAAUAUUCAUGGCUAUAUGAAAGACAUUGAGAAUUAUAUUCAAGAUGGGAAAGACGACUAUAAGAAGCAAAAAGAAACUGAACUUAAUAAAGUAAUAGCUCAACUAAGUGAAUGCGAGAAACACAAAGAAAAGAUAAAUGAAGAUAUGAGACUCAUGAGACAAGAUAUUGAUACACAGAAGAUACAAGAAAGGUGGCUACAAGAUAACCUUACUUUAAGAAAAAGAAAUGAGGAACUAAAAGAAGUUGAAGAAGAAAGAAAACAACAUUUGAAGGAAAUGGGUCAAAUGCAGGUUUUGCAAAUGAAAAGUGAACAUCAGAAGUUGGAAGAGAACAUAGACAAUAUAAAAAGAAAUCAUAAUUUGGCAUUAGGGCGACAGAAAGGUUAUGAAGAAGAAAUUAUUCAUUUUAAGAAAGAACUUCGAGAACCACAAUUUCGGGAUGCUGAGGAAAAGUAUAGAGAAAUGAUGAUUGUUAUGAGGACAACAGAACUUGUGAACAAGGAUCUGGAUAUUUAUUAUAAGACUCUUGACCAAGCAAUAAUGAAAUUUCACAGUAUGAAAAUGGAAGAAAUCAAUAAAAUUAUACGUGACCUGUGGCGAAGUACCUAUCGUGGACAAGAUAUUGAAUACAUAGAAAUACGGUCUGAUGCCGAUGAAAAUGUAUCAGCUUCUGAUAAAAGGCGGAAUUAUAACUACCGAGUGGUGAUGCUGAAGGGAGACACAGCCUUGGAUAUGCGAGGACGAUGCAGUGCUGGACAAAAGGUAUUAGCCUCACUCAUCAUUCGCCUGGCCCUGGCUGAAACGUUCUGCCUCAACUGUGGCAUCAUUGCCUUGGAUGAGCCAACAACAAAUCUUGACCGAGAAAACAUUGAAUCUCUUGCACAUGCUCUGGUUGAGAUAAUAAAAAGUCGCUCACAGCAGCGUAACUUCCAGCUUCUGGUAAUCACUCAUGAUGAAGAUUUUGUGGAGCUUUUAGGACGUUCUGAAUAUGUGGAGAAAUUCUACAGGAUUAAAAAGAACAUCGAUCAGUGCUCAGAGAUUGUGAAAUGCAGUGUUAGCUCCCUGGGAUUCAAUGUUCAUUAAAAAUAUCCAAGAUUUAAAUGCCAUAGAAAUGUAGGUCCUCAGAAAGUGUAUAAUAAGAAACUUAUUUCUCAUAUCAACUUAGUCAAUAAGAAAAUAUAUUCUUUCAAAGGAACAUUGUGUCUAGGAUUUUGGAUGUUGAGAGGUUCUAAAAUCAUGAAACUUGUUUCACUGAAAAUUGGACAGAUUGCCUGUUUCUGAUUUGCUGCUCUUCAUCCCAUUCCAGGCAGCCUCUGUCAGGCCUUCAGGGUUCAGCAGUACAGCCGAGACUCGACUCUGUGCCUCCCUCCCCAGUGCAAAUGCAUGCUUCUUCUCAAAGCACUGUUGAGAAGGAGAUAAUUACUGCCUUGAAAAUUUAUGGUUUUGGUAUUUUUUUAAAUCAUAGUUAAAUGUUACCUCUGAAUUUACUUCCUUGCAUGUGGUUUGAAAAACUGAGUAUUAAUAUCUGAGGAUGACCAGAAAUGGUGAGAUGUAUGUUUGGCUCUGCUUUUAACUUUAUAAAUCCAGUGACCUCUCUCUCUGGGACUUGGUUUCCCCAACUAAAAUUUGAAGUAGUUGAAUGGGGUCUCAAAGUUUGACAGGAACCUUAAGUAAUCAUCUAAGUCAGUACCCACCACCUUCUUCUCCUACAUAUCCCUUCCAGAUGGUCAUCCAGACUCAGAGCUCUCUCUACAGAGAGGAAAUUCUCCACUGUGCACACCCACCUUUGGAAAGCUCUGACCACUUGAGGCCUGAUCUGCCCAUCGUGAAGAAGCCUGUAACACUCCUCUGCGUCUAUCCUGUGUAGCAUACUGGCUUCACCAUCAAUCCUGAUUCCUCUCUAAGUGGGCAUUGCCAUGUGGAAGGCAAGCCAGGCUCACUCACAGAGUCAAGGCCUGCUCCCUGUAGGGUCCAACCAGACCUGGAAGAACAGGCCUCUCCAUUUGCUCUUCAGAUGCCACUUCUAAGAAAAGCCUAAUCACAGUUUUUCCUGGAAUUGCCAGCUGACAUCUUGAAUCCUUCCAUUCCACACAGAAUGCAACCAAGUCACACGCUUUUGAAUUAUGCUUUGUAGAGUUUUGUCAUUCAGAGUCAGCCAGGACCAUACCGGGUCUUGAUUCAGUCACAUGGCAUGGUUUUGUGCCAUCUGUAGCUAUAAUGAGCAUGUUUGCCUAGACAGCUUUUCUCAACUGGGUCCAGAAGAGAAUUAAGCCCUAAGGUCCUAAGGCAUCUAUCUGUGCUAGGUUAAAUGGUUGGCCCCCAAAGAUAGACAGGUCCUGAUUUCUAGAACCCGUGACUGUUACUUUAUACAGCAAAGGAAACUUUGCAGAUGUGAUUAAAGCUAAGGACCUUAAGACAGAGUAUCCUGGGGGUGGUGGUGGGGUGGGGGGGGGUCCUAAAUGUAAUCACGAGUAAGAUUAAGAGCAAAUCAAUUCUAGUCAUAUAUUAAACAUCCACAAUAACCAAGAUAUUUUUAUCCCAAGAAUGCAAGAUUUCAGAAAAUGAAAAAUCUGUUGAUAAAUCCAUCACUAUAAUAAAACCGAAGGUGAAAAAAAUUCUGAAAAAAUUCUAGCAGCUAUAUUUGAUAAAAUUCAACAUCUCCUAGCUUUAGCAAACUCACAGUUUUGCAAAUAAUAUUUUCUUAAUGUUAUCUGUUGCUAAAUCAAAAUUAAACAGUCAUCUUAACUGCAAAAUAAAACAUUUCUCAGUAAAUAUUAAAGCCAGUUACCUUCUAUCAACAUGUUAAUGAAAGUGCUAGUUGUUGCAGCAAAGAAUAACAAAGGCAAUACACGAUCAAUAUAGGCAGUGAAACAAAAGUAUCAUUUGCAAGUUAAAACAGACUUCCCAAUUUUAAAUCUGGUUUCCCCCUGAAUAUGUGGCAUCCUUGGCAGCACUUCUGAGAGUGGCUGCUUUCAUUCCAAGAAGCCCAUGGGUUUGGAGGUGGGAUAGGUGCCUUUCUGGCUUCUCAUUGCUGCUUCUAGAUCAGUCUCCAAAUAUCCCCCUUCCCCACAUUGGAAUGAAUAGCCAUCACAGCAUGGAUGGAGGUUAGAAUGAGCCAGACUGCCUGGGCUCAAAUCCUAGCACACCACUCACUAGCUGGGGACCUUGAGCAAGUUAUUUGUCCUGUUUUCUGUUUCCUUAUAUGUAAAAGUGGGUAAAAUGGUACAUAUUUUGUAGGGUUGUUAUGAAGAUUGAAUGACAUUAUUUACAAACUGCUUAGAACUGCUUGCCACCUACUAAAUACUGUGUAAGUGUUCAAGAAAAAGCUGUCUUCAUUUCACUCUUGUUGCAGUUAUCUUUCAUUCCCAGCUUGGUCACUCCCUCUUAUUUGUUGAAGAGUUUAGCUCCCGGUUCAGUGUCACCCCAUUACUAAUAAUCAUUGCUGAUUUCAAUAUCCAAGUGAUGGUCUAAUACAACUCCUUGGCCUCUCAGUCUUUUUUAUUUUUUGAGGUGGAGUCUUGCUCUGUCACCCAGGCUGGAGUGCAAUGGCACCAUCUCAGCUCACUGCAACCUCUGCCUCCCUGAUACAAGCAAUCCUCCUGCCUCAGCCUCCCAAGUAGCUAGGAUUACAGGCAUGUACCACCACACCAGGCUAAUUUUUGUAUUUUAGUAGAGACAGGGUUUCGCCUUGUUGGCCAGGCUGGUCUUGAACGUCUGGCCUCAAGUGAUCUGCCUACCUUGGCCUCCCUCAGCCCCUUUUUGUUUCCUCCAGUGAGAAGAUACUCAGUUCUAUGGUCUUAUUCUAGAGCCCCGUCCUUUUAAUAACAAUAACUGCACCCCUCCAAAAUCUCAGUUUUAAGCAUCUCACUCUCCAAUAACCCCAUGGUGUCUACAAUUUUCCUGUGGUCCUCAACCCCAGCAAUUCUUUGACCCCACUGAGAUUUCAAUCCAUUGAUUCUAUGGCUUUUUCACAGGUUGUUUCCCUGAUGCCUGUACUUCUCUCCUUAUUCAACUUAAAUUCCAUGGCUCAUCAUUAUGUCACCCUCCACUGCAUUGUACUCAAACUGUCCCGACAAUCCCCAGCCCUACUGGAAUCCAGCUCUGCCUCCUCCCUGCAACACCUGCACAUCCCGUUUCCUUUGCUGUUUCCUCCUCAUUUCCCUGGCCCCUCAAUGUCACAGGUUUUAGUACUCAGAGUCUGCACCUCUUUUCUUCUCUGUGCUCACUUAUUUGGUGAUCUCAUCCAGUCUCAUAGCUUUAAAUUAUCUUAGUUUGGGUUCUCCCAGAAGCAGAGCGUAAAACAAUGCUUCACGUGAAAGUAAUCAGUAGGAAAUUGGGGAAAUUGUGUAUGAAAGAGAAAGCAGCCAAUGAAAAGUUUACUAUUAAGCCAGCUACGGUAAGUGGGCAAUUAGAGUUUGGUGCCCCAGGGAGACUCUGGGGAGUUUGGCAAAAUAUAUACCUCAGAAUUAUCCCACCUAAGGGGCAAGAGACCUGGAGUAUUUAUAUAACAACUUGCCAGGGUUACUGAGUGAAGGCUAUUCUAGCACAUGUUAGUUACUGGCUUGCCAUGUGUACCGACACAGCUGCUUUCCACAGUUUAAAAAGAAAGUCUGAGCAACAUAGUGACAUCCCAUCUUUACAUAAAAUUUUUAAAAAAUUAGCAAGGCAUGGUGGUGCACACCUGUAGUCUCAGCUACUUGGCUGAGAUAGGAUCCCUGGAGUCUGAGGGUUCAAGGCUGCAGUGAGCUGUGAUUUGUGCCACUGCACCCCAGCCUGGGUGGGUGGCAGAGUGAGACCCUGUCUAAAAAGACAAAAAAAAAAAAAAAAAAAAAGCAGCAGCAGCUGAAAGUUGGCAGGAGCACACUGGCAGUUCCUAGGAUCAUAGGAUAUAGGCAGGGCACUGACCACUCCUACAACCACCAUCUAUACACUGAUAACUCAUAAAUGUUUGUGUCCAAUCCAGAUCUCUCCUAAAUGCUUGACUGAUAUAUUCAGCUGCCUGUGGAUAACUGGGCAUCUAUCUGCACUUGAAUAUCUAAUAAACGUCUAAAACUUAAAAUGACCAAAA